AGACGUCCCUGGGUUCCGGUGUUCGCGGAGGAGUCGAGGCACGGAGAGGCUUCGGGGGAGGGACGGAAAGAAGGGUGGCCCGCCAGGCGGGCGGGGUCCAUGGAUUCGGGGUGAGGGCCGUCCGCGGCCUCGCUUUCGCCUCCUCCGAGCCGGGCCGGCGAUGGCCGCAGCUGUGAGGCGAGGUCGGGUCCCGUAGCGGCGCGCAGCCUCCUUGGGGGACUCGGGGUCCUGGUUAGUUUCCACAGCUCCUUCUAUCUGAGGGGUACGAAUUUACGGCUGCCUAAAGCCUUAGAACAGUGAUCCCACGUCGGUAAUUUUAGAACCCGGUAGGACCGGCUGCCAUCAGGGGCCCCAGGUGCAGGGUGGUGUCAGCUUUGAGAGGAAUUGGAGCCUCGUCACCGCGCGCUUCCUGCAUGAGUGGAACCUCAGAAAACGGUCAGCGGGGUUCAGAAGGCAGGAGAUAACACCAAGACCCUACGUAGGAUUGCAUCUUUACGUCGUAGGCUUGGUCUCGUGUAUUUUUAUUGAGCGUGUUUAAUUAGCUGAGGUUACUCGCUUUGGCACCCCAGUGAUCGUUUUUGCCACCAAGCUCUGCCUCUUGAGCGUUUAAUACUGGGAUUUACAAAGCAACGGGUUCCUGUUAAUCUUAGCUUUCAAUACUGGGCAAGGGUUACGUUUCUAACCCUACCAGUGCCGCAGGCUCAUUAUAUAUUGAAGGACUCACCUGGUAUUUGGUUUUCUCAUUUAUAAAGUGGAGUUGGAGUAGGUACUUGAAGGGUUUUCAAUACCUUUAAAUUCUGAAUUUUAAACUCUAAAACUUAAUGAUACCGUAGGACUUUAAGAGAGUAUAGGUUUUAAAAGCUCUUACCUUGAUAUUAAUGACAGUGGUCUACUGUGUAGAAACUUGAGAUUAAAUUGCAGACUGCAGCUAUGACCGGACCAUUUUUAGUGUGAUGCAAACUGUAUCUUCUGCAGGUUAUAGGCAUUUUGGAAGCAGGAACUGAGAAAAUUCUGGCAGUGAUCUUUCAGUAUUUUAAAUUCCACCAUUUCUCCAAGUUCAGUUGUCUUGAUGAGAUACAGGGUGGAACUUAUUUCAAACAUCUCUUGAUGCCAGAAUUGAACGGGAACAGAAAAGGGCUGUAGUAAGAACCAUCAUCAAAGCCUCCAGGACUUGAGCAGCGACUGACGUUUUUACUUCUAACCCUGGAUAUCUCAGAGAUUUGGUUCCACUGUGCUUUUCUAUCUCUCCACUCACGCCUUAUAUAUUUUGAAUACAUCUGUCUUCAUAAAAUACACCAUGUCCAAAAUCUAAAAGGGCCAAUUCCAAAUUAUUCCACCAGCUUUGAAGGGAAUUGAAGCAAGAAUAACAAGACAGAAGAAUAGAAGGAAGGUGAUAGGAUGUGAUGAUAGAAUUUGUGAUAGCCAAGCAACAACUUUUCCUAAUUCGGCAUGUUAAAAAAUAAGGGUCACUCAUCUAAGAAAGAUAACUUGGCAGUCAAUGCAGUUGCUUUACAAGAUCACAUUUUACAUGAUCUUCAACUUCGAAAUCUUUCAGUUGCAGAUCAUUCUAAGACACAAGUACAAAAGAAAGAGAACAAAUCUCUAAAAAGAGAUACAAAGGCAAUAAUAGAUACUGGACUUAAAAAAACUACACAGUGCCCCAAACUAGAAGACUCAGAAAAAGAAUAUGUUCUUGAUCCCAAACCGCCGCCGUUGACUUUGGCACAGAAGUUGGGCCUCAUUGGGCCUCCACCACCUCCACUGUCAUCAGAUGAAUGGGAGAAGGUGAAACAGCGCUCUCUCCUGCAAGGGGACUCCGUGCAACCAUGCCCCAUCUGUAAAGAAGAAUUCGAGCUUCGUCCUCAGGUGCUGCUUUCAUGCUCCCAUGUGUUCCACAAAGCAUGUCUUCAGGCUUUUGAAAAGUUCACAAAUAAGAAAACCUGUCCUCUCUGUAGAAAGAACCAGUAUCAAACCCGAGUGAUACACGAUGGGGCCCGCCUGUUCAGAAUCAAGUGUGUGACCAGAAUCCAAGCCUACUGGAGAGGAUGUGUUGUUAGAAAGUGGUACAGAAACCUGAGGAAAACAGUACCUCCCACAGAUGCCAAGUUAAGAAAAAAAUUCUUUGAAAAAAAGUUCACAGAAAUCAGCCACCGCAUCCUGUGCUCAUACAACACCAACAUUGAAGAGCUCUUUGCAGAAAUCGAUCAGUGCUUGGCCAUAAAUCGAAGUGUUCUUCAGCAGUUGGAAGAAAAAUGUGGCCAUGAGAUCACAGAAGAGGAAUGGGAGAAAAUCCAAGUGCAGGCUCUGCGCCGGGAGACCCACGAGUGCUCCAUCUGCCUGGCCCCUCUCUCCGCUGCUGGCGGUCAGCGCGUGGGUGCAGGCAGGCGUUCCAGAGAGAUGGCCCUCCUGUCCUGCUCACAUGUGUUCCACCAUGCGUGUCUGCUGGCACUAGAGGAGUUCUCCGUGGGAGACAGGCCUCCUUUCCAUGCCUGUCCUCUCUGCCGCUCCUGCUACCAGAAGAAGAUUCUUGAAUGUUGAAUUCAUAGUCAAGGAAAGUUAGGUAAUUCUGAGGAAAAAAGUUUACCAUCAUUUUGGAUGAACUGCAUGAGUUCUGGGUUAAGUACUACAAUGUAAUCUGUUUCCCAGGGAAAUAAGCUAUUGGUAGUUGUAGGAAAUCUUAGUAUAUUUUAAAAGCUGACAUCCCACCUAAUUUUAAUCUUUGGUCUCUAAAAAGUAAAUUUCAAAUUUAUGAGUUUAAUCACUUCAAAUAUGAAUAGCAAAAAAUGAGAGCUUGCUUACUUCUAAAAAUUGAGGUUAAGAUAUAGCUAGUGUCUGAACGACACUCCUUAAAGUAAGUUCCAAAUGUAAAACACUCCUUAAGUUCCAAAUGUUUUCCGCUAAUAGUCUGUCCUAAAGCCUUUGCCAUUCCUAAUACUCGUUUUGUAAUAAUUGCUGUAUUUCUGUGUAAUAAAAUAUAAAAAUAAAAUAUUCAGUGGUAUUCAACAUCAAAAAA